AGUCCCAGCUCUGCCAGGAAAGGGGAGACUUCACCGUGGCACUGGGAAUUGGAUUCUAAACUUUAGGAUCAAGCAAUGGAAGGACCUGGAAUAAGACACCUUCUUGACCCCCCUGAAGGGCUCUGAGCAGCUGGGCUUGCCUUUCUCUUUGCUCCCCCAGUCCUCCCCUUACUUCUCGGUCUCCCACUCCCCAUCACUCCUUUCCCUGCCUCCUCCUGCCUGUCUCCAUCUUCCUCCCUCUCUUUCUUCUCUCGCCCCAUUAAUCCCCGCUUGUCACUAUCACCUCCUUCCUCCAGUCUUUCCCCCUUCGCUGCCCCUUCUUUCCUCUGACAUUUCCUUCUCCUCUUACUGCCACUGUCUCCCACCUUUCUCCUCCCCCACAUUUCUCCCUAUCCCUACCUCCUCUUCCCCUUCAUCUUUCUCCUUCCCCCUUAUUUUUCUAUCUCCUUCCUCAGUCCCACUCCUCUUUCCACCCUCCUUUUGCCCGUCACUUCUCCUUCUCCCUCACUGCCCCCUCCCUCUCUCUCCCCUCCCCAGGUCCUGCCCCACCCAGCUGUGUUUGCUUUUCUCCCGGAUCCGGAUGGAGGGGUUGCCCUGCCCGUGCCCAGCCCUGCCCCACUUCUGGCAGCUUAGGUCUCACUUAAUGGCUGAGGGCUCCAGGACUCAGGCCCCUGGGAAAGGGCCCCCACUCAGCAUCCAGUUCCUGCGAGCCCAGUAUGAAGGCUUGAAGAGGCAGCAGAGGACCCAGGCCCACCUCCUGGUGCUUCCAAAAGGAGGAAACACACCUGCUCCUGCAGAAUCGAUGGUCAAUGCUGUUUGGAUUAACAAGGAGAGAAGAAGCUCACUGUCCCUGGAAGAGGCAGAUUCUGAGGUGGAGGGGAGGCUGGAGGAGGCUGCCCAGGGCUGCCUUCAGGCCCCCAAGUCUCCAUGGCACACGCACCUGGAGAUGCAUUGUUUGGUCCAAACCUCCCCCCAGGACACCAGUCAUCAAGUACAUCAUAGGGGCAAGCUUGUGGGAUCUGAUCAAAGGCUCCCUCCUGAAGGAGACACACACUUGUUUGAAACCAAUCAGAUGACUCAGCAAGGAACCGGAAUCCCAGAGGCUGCCCAGCUUCCAUGCCAGGUGGGCAAUACCCAAACAAAGGCAGUGGAAUCUGGCUUAAAAUUCAGCACUCAAUGUCCUCUUUCCAUAAAGAACCCACACAGGUCUGGCAAACCAGCUUACUAUCCAUUUCCCCAGAGGAAAACACCCAGGAUCUCCCAAGCUGCCCGGAACCUGGGCUUAUAUGGCUCAGCGUGAAGCUUUCUAUUCUGCCAGAUGUCUUGACCUUGAGGCCACCUAUGGCCUUAUAGAAGAACCAAGGAGGCAGAGCCACAACGAGGUCUCUAGCUAUGAGCAAGAACUGGACUAACCUAAUUAUAGGAAUUGUGGGAGACGAACUUCACAAUGGUAACAUGGUUUUACCCUUCCAAUAAGAAGAGACUUCCCAGGCCAAAUUGCCCACAGUUUAGGAUGAAGAGGACUGUCUGGUCAGUGCAGCCCCAUUCUGACAUUACUAUGAGGUCCUGGAUAUCCAUUCCUUGGGGAGGACCAGUAAGACAUCUGCUCCAUCCCUGGAACUGGAUAAUUUUGGAACAUAAACCAGGGACCUAGCCAACAGAAUGCCUUAGCAAUGCCCAGGGGUCAAUGGGCGUGGCAUUCUUGUUUUCAAUGUCUUCUGAUGAUUUCUCAUAUAUUCUGGAGAAGACAAGCUCUGAGAAUUCAGAUGCUUUUUCUGGUGGCUAUGUCUGGGGGGCCAUCUCACUUAGAAGUCACAACACUCAUUGGCAGUGAUCACAUCAUUUCAAUUUGGGCUUCCCAAAGUAUGGUCACCCAGGGUAUGAAGGUGAGAUCAAUGCUACCUACCAUUUUGUGUCUUUAAGGGGUCUUUAGAAAGGGCUAAUCAUCUGUCACUGCUCACUGAGACAUGUACAUUCCAGCAUCAUCACAGAGUUAUCUCCUUCCUUCCUUCCUUCCUUCCUUCCUUCCUUCCUUCUGUCUCUCCCUCCCUCCCUCCCUUCCUCCCUUCUUUCCUUCUUUCUUUCCUCUCUUCCUUCUUGCCUUCUUUCCUGCCUUCCUGCCUAUCUUUUCUCUCUCUCUCUCUCUGCAAAUUAAGUUCUUAUUAAAAACUGCCAAUCAUUGACGAUAUAUAAUGAUGAGAUCCUGAACAAAAGAGGCAAAGAAAUGCUCCUACUUGAAAAAUACACAUUCCCUAUAGACUGCCUCCUGUUUAGUCCAACUUAGAUCACUCAGAUCCUUCCUGGGAUCAAAUAUAUUUUUAAACCUAAGACAAAGCGAAGCAGGUGUCACUUGGGUGAUAGGGAAAAAAGCUUGUAUUUCCUGGUUAAUGUUUAGCUUUUGUAAUGCUAUUUAAACACACCUAAGGUGCCUUUCCCUCAUCUCAGGUGCUUUCUCUGUAAAGUUUCACUCCCACCUUUCUUUUCUCUGCAUGGCCGUCCAGUCUUGCCCAUCUACAUCCAGAGCUGUUAACUAGUAGUGUCAUUACCUGUGAAAAACAUGUAGAAGCUUCCUUGAACCACCCAGAAAUCCACUCAAAUUUGGGGAUUGUCAUUCCUUUUGUGAAUAAUUAAUACAAUUCAGUUGUUUUUUAAAUAUUCUAAUAAAAAAGGAAAUUUUCUCAAAAAAA